AGCUCCAGUCAGGCCCCAUCCGGGCCCUUCCAGAAGCAACCCAGGAGCCCCGAGACCUGCAGGGAUGUGUGCACCCUGACCCCUGACGCAUAGCCCUGCACCUGCAGCCAGCUGGCCUCGGGCUUGAAAACAUGGCGGGUGCGCUCCAAUUCACGGUGGUUUCCAAGCGCAUUCUGGAGGAGAAAACACAUGAGUGUGUGGUCAGGGUUCUCUGCUGACAGACCUACCGUGGGGAAGAAAGAGAAGCUCUGAAGAUGGAUCAUGGCCGUGACUGCAUGUCAAGGAGAAUCUCCAUGAUGACACGGAGGCCUACGUCGAGAUAGAGUAAAUAUGGUCCAAUUAAAAGGUUAGGGUACGUUCCACGUCAGGUGACCAGAGGCAGUAUAAAAGGCAGCCUGGAAAGCAGAGGUCCCUCUCUGCCCCUUCCUCCGUCUUCCUGGAUGCUGCAUCGCUUCCAGCGGGGCUGCUCCAGCACCUGCCCAUCUCAGCGCCAGCCGGGGAAAGAAAGUAGACGUGUAAUUUCAGGUGACCCGACAAUCAACCCCUGAAAAAGGCGGUCAUAAAACCCCCAGGAGACGAAGAUGAUGGCACGUCGUGACCCCAAACCUGGGGCAAAGAGACUGGUGAGAGCCCAGACCCUCCAGAAGCAGCGGAGGGCCCCAGUUGGGCCAAGGGCUCCCCCGCCCGAUGAAGAAGAUCCCAGGCUCAAGUGCAAAAACUGUGAGGCCUUUGGCCACACGGCCAGAAGUACCAGGUGCCCCAUGAAGUGCUGGAAGGCAGCCCUGGUUCCACCGAACUUUGGGGAAAAGGAAGGGAAGGAAAACCUGAAACCAUGGAAGCCCCAGGUUGAAGCGAACCCUGGGCCCUUGAACAAGGAUAAGGGAGAGAAGGAAGAGAGACCAAGGCCACAAGACCCGCAGAGGAAGGCUCUCCUCCACAUAUUUUCCAGGAAACCUCCAGAGAAGCCGCUGCCAAAUCAAAAAGGAUCCACGGAAUCUUCUGAUUAUCUGAGGGUUGCAAGCGGGCCAAUGCCGGUCCACACAACCAGUAAGAGGCCGCGUGUGGACCCUGUCCUCUCUGAUCGCUCAGCUACCGAAAUGUCUGACAGGGGCUCCGUCUUAGCUUCACUGUCUCCCCUCAGAAAAGCCAGUCUGAGCUCCUCCUCAAGUCUUGGACCAAAGGAAAGACAGACAGGGGCUGCGGCCGACAUCCCUCAGACUGCAGUCAGGCACCAGGGCCCCGAGCCUCUCCUCGUGGUGAAGCCGACACACAGCAGCCCUGCGGGUGGCUGUCGAGAAGUUCCCCAGGCUGCCUCCAAAACCCACGGCCUGCUCCAGGCCGUCAGCCCCCAGGCACAAGACAAACGUCCUGCGGUGACCUCACAGCCCUGCCCACCAGCCGCCACACACAGCUUGGGCCUAGGCUCCAAUCUCAGCUUCGGGCCAGGAGCCAAGAGAUCUGCCCCGGCUCCGAUUCAGGCUUGCCUGAACUUCCCCAAGAAACCGAGACUGGGUCCCUUCCAGAUCCCCGAAAGCGCCAUCCAGGGAGGUGAGCUGGGGGCCCCGGAGAAUCUCCAACCUCCGCCAGCCGCAACCGAACUUGGACCACGUACGUCACCCCAGACAGGCACGAGGACACCCGCCCAGGUGCUUAGCGGCGACCGGCAGCCUCCGCACAGCAGACCUUGCCUGCCUACUGCCCAGGCCUGCACCAUGUCCCAUCACCCAGCGGCCAGCCAUGAUGGGGCCCAGCCUCUCAGAGUGCUCUUUCGGAGACUGGAAAACGGACGCUGGAGCUCCAGCCUGCUGACGGCCCCCUCAUUUCACUCUCCUGAGAAGCCGGGAGCCUUCCUCGCUCAGAGCCCUCAUGUCUCAGAGAAGUCUGAGGGUCCCUGUGUUCGUGUCCCACCAAGCGUCCUCUAUGAGGACCUUCAGGUUCCCUCCUCCUCAGAGGACAGCGAUUCUGACCUGGAGUGAGACUGCAGGUGGCAGGGGCUCCUUGGCCUCCAGCUCCCGUGACUUGGAGGGGACUGUGGGACUGAGGAGCACAGAGCAGAGAGCAGACUCUGUGCGGUGACUCCGAAGCUCCCCGGCUGUGGCCCUUCUGUGGAUGUGGGAGCCCAGGCCAGGCAGGGAGCAGAUGCAGGGACUCUGCCACGUUGAAUUCUGGUGAGGGACAUUGUAGUUCGCAUGGUUCUCUGGAAACGCGCCAGGAAAAGCUUCCGUGCCAGUGAUUCGUUGCCUCAGAAACUGCAUGACGCGCAGGAGUCAGACUUCCGCUGGGACGUCAAUAGGAAACGGGGGAAUUACUGUGUAUUUGCUCUCUAGACGACUGAAUAAGGGAAAAGUUAGGGAACCCUGAGAGGUGCAGCCCUUCCGCUGUGCCCCGCCCUGAGAGCAGUGUUUCGGACGCUGGGAAGCGCGCUGUGCAAAGCGCUCUCGGGGUCUUUCCUCAGCCUCGAAAAGUGGGCUCUGGAAUCCCUUUGUAAAUAGGUGUGUUGAAUUUGUUUUGAAGUGAAUAAAAUUCUCAAAAAGAUGA